GAUUACAGACAUGAGCCACCUCGCCCAGCCUUUUCAUGGCUGAGUGAUAUUCCAUUGUGUGGAUGGAUCACACUAGCUACUCUGACCCAUGGAUCCCCUGGGCCCAGCCAAGCCACAGUGGCUGUGGCGCCGCUGUCUGGCCGGGCUGCUGUUUCAGCUGCUGGUGGCUGUGUGUUUCUUCUCCUACCUGCGUGUGUCCCGAGACGAUGCCACUGGAUCCCCUAGGCCAGGGCUUAUGGCAGUGGAACCUGUCACCGGGGCUCCCAAUGGGUCCCGCUGCCAGGACAGCAUGGCGACCCCUGCCCACCCCACCCUACUGAUCCUGCUGUGGACGUGGCCUUUUAACACACCCGUGGCUCUGCCCCGCUGCUCAGAGAUGGUGCCCGGCGCGGCCGACUGCAACAUCACUGCCGACUCCAGUGUGUACCCACAGGCAGACGCGGUCAUCGUGCACCACUGGGAUAUCAUGUACAACCCCAGUGCCAACCUCCCGCCCCCCACCAGGCCGCAGGGGCAGCGCUGGAUCUGGUUCAGCAUGGAGUCCCCCAGCAACUGCCGGCACCUGGAAGCCCUGGACGGAUACUUCAAUCUCACCAUGUCCUACCGCAGCGACUCCGACAUCUUCACGCCCUACGGCUGGCUGGAGCCGUGGUCCGGCCAGCCUGCCCACCCACCGCUCAACCUCUCGGCCAAGACCGAGCUGGUGGCCUGGGCGGUGUCCAACUGGAAGCCGGACUCGGCCAGGGUGCGCUACUACCAGAGCCUGCAGGCUCAUCUCAAGGUGGACGUGUACGGACGCUCCCACAAGCCCCUGCCCAAGGGGACCAUGAUGGAGACGCUGUCCCGGUACAAGUUCUAUCUGGCCUUCGAGAACUCCUUGCACCCCGACUACAUCACCGAGAAGCUGUGGAGGAACGCCCUGGAGGCCUGGGCCGUGCCCGUGGUGCUGGGCCCCAGCAGAAGCAACUACGAGAGGUUCCUGCCACCCGACGCCUUCAUCCACGUGGACGACUUCCAGAGCCCCAAGGACCUGGCCCGGUACCUGCAGGAGCUGGACAAGGACCACGCCCGCUACCUGAGCUACUUUCACUGGCGGGAGACGCUGCGGCCUCGCUCCUUCAGCUGGGCACUGGCUUUCUGCAAGGCCUGCUGGAAGCUGCAGCAGGAAUCUAGGUACCAGACGGUGCGCAGCAUAGCGGCUUGGUUCACCUGAGAGGCCGGCAUGGGGCCUGGGCUGCCGGGACCUCACUUUCCCAGGGCCUCACCUACCUAGGGUCUCACUAGUCGGGGGAUUUACCUACCUGGGGCCUCGGCUGCCUGGGGCCUCGGCUGCCUGGGGUCUCACCUGCCUGGGGCCUCACCUGCUGGAGUCUUUGGUGGCCAGGCAUGUGACUUACCUGGGAUUUCACUUGCCGGGCUUCACUGCCAGGAGCCUCCCCUGCUGGGGACCUUGCCAGCUGGGGCUGGGGAUGGUGCCUACUGGGGACCUUGCUUUCUGGAGGCUGCACCUACUGAGGAUCUCGGCUGUUGGGGACUUUACCUGCUGGGACCUGCUCCCAGAGACCUUGCCACACUGAAUGUCACCUGCUAGGAGCCUCACCCGCUGGGAGGCACAGGGCCCAAGGGAGCUGGAUGUGUUGCCCAAGGUGUGCAGGGCAGGUCAGGGAAGGGCAGGGUCCCCUAAGGAGGAGGGCGAAGGGUAUGUGUGUGACCAUCAGCAGUGGUGUGCACAUGGCUGGGGGACACUCGGUUUGACCGCCAGCGGAUGGGUGUCACAAAUGCAUCACUAUGGGUGUGACCUCGGCGUGACUCUGAUAGUGCCUGUGGAUGUGUUGCGAUGCCUCACCCUGGAGGGCACUGGGCCCUGAGAACGGGUGCCCUUGAGGCCCUGCCCCCGGGCGAUGGUGCAGGCUGGUUUGCUUGUGGUUUUAUUGCUGUUGUUAACCACCCAUGAGGGGUGCAAACAGAUAAUGCUGUUAACAUUUUCA